GUGUCCAGUUGGUUGCCGCGGCAGUCUCUCCGAGCAGCGCAUUUGUCUUCUAGGCUGCUUGGUUCGUGCCUCCGAGAAAGGGGUCUCCUGCUGCCAGCUAAGUGUGGGAGAACUUGUGCACGUAUCUCCCCUCCGAAUCCCAACGAUGGGUAACGCCAGCUUUGGCUCCAAGGAACAGAAGCUGCUGAAGCGGUUGCGGCUUCUGCCCGCCCUGCUUAUCCUCCGCGCCUUCAAGCCCCACAGGAAGAUCAGAGAUUACCGCGUCGUGGUAGUCGGCACCGCUGGUGUGGGGAAAAGUACGCUGCUGCACAAGUGGGCGAGCGGCAACUUCCGUCAUGAGUACCUGCCGACCAUUGAAAAUACCUACUGCCAGUUGCUGGGCUGCAGCCACGGUGUGCUUUCCCUGCACAUCACCGACAGCAAGAGUGGCGACGGCAACCGCGCUCUGCAGCGCCACGUUAUAGCCCGGGGCCACGCCUUCGUCCUGGUCUACUCAGUCACCAAGAAGGAAACCCUGGAAGAGCUGAAGGCCUUCUAUGAGCUGAUCUGCAAGAUCAAAGGUAACAACCUGCAUAAGUUCCCCAUCGUGCUGGUGGGCAAUAAAAGUGAUGACACCCACCGGGAGGUGGCCCUGAAUGAUGGUGCCACCUGUGCGAUGGAGUGGAAUUGCGCCUUCAUGGAGAUUUCAGCCAAGACCGAUGUGAAUGUGCAGGAGCUGUUCCACAUGCUGCUGAAUUACAAGAAAAAGCCCACCACCGGCCUCCAGGAGCCCGAGAAGAAAUCCCAGAUGCCCAACACCACUGAGAAGCUGCUUGACAAGUGCAUAAUCAUGUGAGCCCUGGGCCUUAAGAGCCAGCUCUUCCUAUCCUGUAGCGUGUAGAAAACGUGGACUCAUUUCACUAUGUUACAUGUACAUGGUUGAUUUUGUGCUGUUGUUUGGACUGUAACAUCCAUGUUGUCAAUACGUAUACCUUGUAAGUGGAUAACUUUUCUUUUUCCCAGGCCAGAGAAUUCAAAUUGUUAAAACAUUGGCAUUUGAAGAGGAGAACAAAAUGUAGCAUGAUGUAUUUAAAGUAAGGCCUUUAGUAAUGAAUGUAAUGAGAGAAAAUGUUUUGAAAAGAACAAAACAUCAAAAUGAAUAGAAAGAAAAAUUGGAAGGCGUCCUUUUGGUAACCCGAUUAUUGUGUAUUACCUUUAAAUAUUUCACAUCCUGUAAGUGCUUAAUCAUAUCUUUUAAUUGUGUAUUUAAGAAAAGUGUUUUCACAACAAAAGCUUUUGAUAAAUUGCUGCGUGACAUAUACUAAAUAAAAAAAUGAAUAUGUUGAUCAUUAGGGGUGUGGGAGCAGAGAAAAUUGUGAAAGUGACUCUCACUAAAGAUGUUAGUAGUUUCUCAUGUCAUUUAAAAAUGUUUGAGUAUUCUGCAUAGCAGUUUGUAAAAGUGUAACAGCUUAUUGACUUAAUAAAGCUUUUCCUGCAUGCAA